GGACCCGUGGGCUUCUGGCAGGACCCGCGCCAUGGACCUCUUAUUUCUGCGCCCUGUGACAAUCUGAGCCGUCUUUCUCUGGGGGAGAAGUUUCUUGCUGGGAGUGGAGGCGACGCCAAGUGGCCUGGGAAGUGGGAAGCCAGAUUGGACCCUACUGACUGGGGACCCUCAGCCUUGGGGCUCCUCUGGAGAAGUGAUCAGUUGCCCUGCUGGAAACUCACAUCCAGGGGGCAGUGGCUGGAGAGCAAGAGCGAACGGUCAGGAAGAGGAGGCCUCCUGCUCCACGACGUGACCAUGGCCGGGCUGCAGGAGCUGCGAUUCCCUGAGGAGAAGCCGCUGCUCCGGGGCCAGGACGCCACCGAGCUGGAGAGCUCCGAUGCCUUCCUCUUGGCUGCAGACACAGACUGGAAGGUGGGGGAAGGCAACGCUGGAGCCGUGAAGCUGGCAGGGCUAGGGGACCCCAGGUGGAGCCCAGGGCACCUCCUCUCGCCGGGGCAUCAGGAACAUGACAUCGAGACACCCUACGGCCUUCUGCAUGUAGUGAUCCGGGGCUCCCCCAAGGGGAACCGCCCAGCCAUCCUCACCUACCAUGAUGUGGGCCUCAACCACAAACUAUGCUUCAACACCUUCUUCAACUUCGAGGACAUGCAGGAGAUCACCAAGCACUUUGUGGUGUGUCACGUGGAUGCCCCUGGACAACAGGUGGGGGCGUCGCAGUUUCCUCAGGGGUACCAGUUCCCCUCCAUGGAGCAGCUGGCUGCCAUGCUCCCCAGCGUGGUGCAGCAUUUCGGGUUCAAGUAUGUGAUUGGCAUCGGAGUGGGCGCCGGAGCCUAUGUGCUGGCCAAGUUUGCACUCAUCUUCCCCGACCUGGUGGAGGGGCUGGUGCUGGUGAACAUCGACCCCAAUGGCAAAGGCUGGAUAGACUGGGCUGCCACCAAGCUCUCCGGCCUAACUAGCACUUUACCCGACACGGUGCUCUCCCACCUCUUCAGCCAGGAGGAGCUGGUGAACAACACAGAGUUGGUGCAGAGCUACCGGCAGCAGAUUGGGAACGUGGUGAACCAGGCCAACCUGCAGCUCUUCUGGAACAUGUACAACAGCCGCAGAGACCUGGACAUUAACCGGCCUGGAACGGUGCCCAAUGCCAAGACGCUCCGCUGCCCCGUGAUGCUGGUGGUUGGGGAUAAUGCACCCGCUGAGGACGGGGUGGUGGAGUGCAACUCCAAACUGGACCCGACCACUACGACCUUCCUGAAGAUGGCAGACUCUGGAGGGCUGCCCCAGGUCACACAGCCAGGGAAGCUGACUGAAGCCUUCAAAUACUUCCUGCAAGGCAUGGGCUACAUUGCGUACUUGAAGGACCGAAGGCUGAGUGGAGGAGCAGUGCCCUCAGCCAGCAUGACCCGCCUGGCACGCUCCCGCACUGCAUCCCUCACCAGUGCCAGCUCGGUGGAUGGCAGCCGCCCACAGGCCUGCACCCACUCAGAGAGCAGCGAGGGGCUGGGCCAGGUCAACCACACCAUGGAGGUGUCCUGUUGAAGCCCUUGAUCCCGCUGACGACGCCCACGUCGAGGCCCCACCGCCAUCCUUGCGCCGGCUCAUGUUCCCUUUAGUUUAUUUUUGUGAGGGCAAAGGGGAGGAAAUGGGGUUCUGUUUGAAAAAAAUGAGGGGAUCUUAGAUGCUGCAGCAGAACAGUCUCCAGGUGUUUUAAGGGGCUCAGUCCUCCUCAUCCCAUCUCACUCUCCGUGGUAACUUAGCCAACUUGACCCCUCUCAUCCCACUCCCGGCGGCCCAGGCACAGAAGGGCAGGGCCAUAGGGAGGGAGAUUCGCUACGGAUCCAGGCCAUUCCUGGGUGAGCCCUUGGGCAGGCAUGUUUGGAGAUGAGAGAGGCUUCGAGAGGGUGGGUGCUGGGCCACAGGGGUGCGGGGCCAGCUCAGGCACUGGCGUGGGAGCCCUGGGAGACCCCUUCCCCCACCCUCCACCAAGCACACCUGUUUCUGUCUCAUAGCACAUGUGACAAUCAUCUGGACAACAGCCACAAGGGGGCGCUCGGACCAGGCAGCCACUUUCCUGGUGCUCUCUGGGCCCAGCUGGUGCUGUAGGGCCACGCAGGCAGGGGCGUCAAGGGGUUUCUCUGCCCAAGGAAGACAGAACAUGGAGAACCGUCAGGGCAGGAACCCCACAGACUGUCCCUUCCAGCCCACACUCUGCCACCUCCUGGCCCUGUCCCAAUUCUGAGCCAAGGCCUCCCCGAGGCAGAAGUUGCCUGGUCCUCUGUCCCCACAGUGACCUGACUGGGGGUGAGGGAGAAGGAGGAGAGAGCCCAUGUGUGGUGUGUGUGCCCCUGAGAACUUCGUGGUGACUGCCUUUGGGAGCCCGCAGGUGGCCAGAGGCAGGGGUAGCUGAGUUCCUGGAGACCCCUUUUUUGCCCCCAGGUUCCCCAGAGGGCAACGCCAUCAGUAGCAGUGUGGUGUUUCAGGCAGAGCUCUGGCCAGGCUGUGCCAGUGUGUCCCGGACGCAUCACUAAGGAAGAGAGAGUUUAUUUAGUCAACUGGCCCAAGGCAGCGAGGCUUCUACAGUCCCACACCCCAUAGCCGCCUGGGCUGGGGCUUACUGGGGGCUGAAGGUUCUGGACAUGAACAAGGGUCAGGUAGAAGAGAAAGGCUUCCCCUACACCCCAGCCUCCUGCUGUCCCCUGAAGCCCAGGACUGCGUUGUAUGCUUUCCAUCCACUCACCUUACCCCAUAGCAUCUUGCGGCCCAGAAACCAGAGCCAUUUGUCUCAGACCCUAAAUCAAUAAUCACAAACCCCAAAACGGGAGAGAGCAGUGAAAACAUGCAGGGCUGUGGACGGGGGAAGGGUUGUGGCGGGUGUUCUGAGGCUGAGAGGACACCUAUAUGCGUAUUUCCUCUACACACAUCACCCCCCUUCUAUAAUCUUAAGCCAUGACUAGCCUGGUGGCGUGUUAGUUUCUGCCCAGUUCUACCCCCUCAUGUGCUUCUUCUGAAUACUGAAUGUGACUGUUUGAAAGCUGGUAGAAUUCAUCCCUCUUACUGUAGAUAACACUGCAAAUCUUGGAAUUUUGUUUUUUGCUGUUUCCAGAUGUAUCUAUAAAUAUCUAUACAUUAUAUGUGUGUGUGUGUGUGUGUGUGUGUGUGUACAUCGGGUCCUCCCAUGUGUGGUGUUCUUCUGGAGGUUGUCUCUUUGGUCAAGGUGAACUUUUAAUGUUUAUUAUUUUCUUCUCCGCACAAAGUAAAGAGCCUAAUUUUGUGUAUUCUGGUGGCUGCUGUCAUGAGAUGAUAAAAUGUAAAACAAAACUCUAGUCAACGUAGAAAGAGUUAACUGUGCUGAAAAACUAAUAAAGAACCUAAGAAGAAUUCCAGUGUGGUGAUGCCAUGCCCAUCAUGGGAGGCUUUUGGAGAAACAGAAUGUUUGGGCAGGGGCUGCUGGUGCUGCUUGGGUUUUGGGUUGAGGGUGCUAGGAGAGGAUGGUCUCCACCCAUCUUUCUAUUUCCAGUACACGUCACAUUAUUUUACCGGUGAGAUGAGAAUGUCACAAACAUUAAAAGCCUUAUGUGCUCA